CCUUUUUGGAGACAGAUUCGCAGUGGUCGCUUCUUCUCCUUGGAUUUGUUAAGGAUUCCAAGUAACUCUUAUUUGGAGAGAAGACGAUCUGCACUUCGCAUUUUGGCAUUGACAUUUAAUUUUAGGGUCCUUUAUAUAGAAGGGAGAGUAGCUACAUGAAUGUGUAAGAUCUUGGAGGAAGACAGCAGAGAGAGAGAGAGAGAUCAGAGAUCCCAGGGUUAAAAGUUGGAGAAAUUUCACAGUACAUCAUCCAAAAGAGGAGUCCAUGAUGGAGGCAGAGGUAAACUUGGAGAGGACAGGAAGAUGUCACCCAAGCGCAUAGCUAAAAGAAGGUCCCCCCCAGCAGAUGCCAUCCCCAAAAGCAAGAAGGUGAAGGUCUCACACAGGUCCCACAGCACAGAACCCGGCUUGGUGCUGACACUAGGCCAGGGCGACGUGGGCCAGCUGGGGCUGGGUGAGAAUGUGAUGGAGAGGAAGAAGCCGGCCCUGGUAUCCAUUCCGGAGGAUGUUGUGCAGGCUGAGGCUGGGGGCAUGCACACCGUGUGUCUAAGCAAAAGUGGCCAGGUCUAUUCCUUCGGCUGCAAUGAUGAGGGUGCCCUGGGAAGGGACACAUCAGUGGAGGGCUCGGAGAUGGUCCCUGGGAAAGUGGAGCUGCAAGAGAAGGUGGUACAGGUGUCAGCAGGAGACAGUCACACAGCAGCCCUCACCGAUGAUGGCCGUGUCUUCCUCUGGGGCUCCUUCCGGGACAAUAACGGUGUGAUUGGACUGUUGGAGCCCAUGAAGAAGAGCAUGGUGCCUGUGCAGGUGCAGCUGGAUGUGCCUGUGGUAAAGGUGGCCUCAGGAAACGACCACUUGGUGAUGCUGACAGCUGAUGGUGACCUCUACACCUUGGGCUGCGGGGAACAGGGCCAGCUAGGCCGUGUGCCUGAGUUAUUUGCCAACCGUGGUGGCCGGCAAGGCCUCGAACGACUCCUGGUCCCCAAGUGUGUGAUGCUGAAAUCCAGGGGAAGCCGGGGCCACGUGAGAUUCCAGGAUGCCUUUUGUGGUGCCUAUUUCACCUUUGCCAUCUCCCAUGAGGGCCACGUGUACGGCUUCGGCCUCUCCAACUACCAUCAGCUUGGAACUCCGGGCACAGAAUCUUGCUUCAUACCCCAGAACCUAACAUCCUUCAAGAAUUCCACCAAGUCCUGGGUGGGCUUCUCUGGUGGCCAGCACCAUACAGUCUGCAUGGAUUCGGAAGGAAAAGCAUACAGCCUGGGCCGGGCUGAGUAUGGGCGGCUGGGCCUUGGAGAGGGUGCUGAGGAGAAGAGCAUACCCACCCUCAUCUCCAGGCUGCCUGCUGUCUCCUCGGUGGCUUGUGGGGCCUCUGUGGGGUAUGCUGUGACCAAGGAUGGUCGUGUUUUCGCCUGGGGCAUGGGCACCAACUACCAGCUGGGCACAGGGCAGGAUGAGGACGCCUGGAGCCCUGUGGAGAUGAUGGGCAAACAGCUGGAGAACCGUGUGGUCUUAUCUGUGUCCAGCGGGGGCCAGCAUACAGUCUUAUUAGUCAAGGACAAAGAACAGAGCUGAUGAAGCCUCUGAGGGCCUGGCUUCUGUCCUGCACAACCUCCCUCACAGAACAGGGAAGCAGUGACAGCUGCAGAUGGCAGCGGGCCUCUCCCCAGCCCUGAGCACUGUGUCAGUUCCUGCCUUUUCUCAUCAGCAGAACAGAAUCCUUUUCCUCUUUUCCUUCCUCCUCUUUGGAAUUUUCCUGGGACCUACAGAAUAAAGGGGGGGAUGGACAGGGGGUUUUCAAAAGGAACAUGGCUCACUCAGAGCUAUAUGGUUAGACGUUUCUCCCCUUUUCCCUACCUUCCAUGGUCCUGGUUGGCCCUGGCUUUGCCUACUAGAAAACCAAAACUUCCCCCCUGGGGUUUUGUGCCCACUCUCUGAGAAGUUGGGGCUCCAUCAAGCCCCAUUCUAGUCAUGUGCCCCUUUCCUGUCCCUAACAGUCCACAGGCAAACAAAUGGUACAGUCAUAAGAGCCAUCUGUCACGGACCCACGCCCAGAGGAACGUGCAGAAAAAAGCAGAGCUACAUGGCUGUGGGCAACUAUAAGCCAAAUAUUUGGCUCAGAACAGGUGUCCAUGGGACAAAAAAGAACGAUCCUCCACUUGACCAAGAAAAAAGUGAUUCUCCCAGAAGCACAAAGCAUACUCUUGCCCCUCAGGUGUUGCUUGUGUACAUCGUACCCAUCCAUUCGGCUUCACCUGCAGCCAACGGCCUGGAAUCGCAAAGAGACACCACUCUGGGCAGAGCAGAGCAGGGUAUGGGGUGGGGAGAGAGGGUGGAGGGUUUUAUAAACAAACUUAACAGCAAUAUUGAAAGGAGGUGGGGGAUUGAGGGAGGGACAGAGUGUUGGAGGGCCAGAGACUAGUCCUGAGAUGGAAACAGCAACUUGUACAGUGGCUGAGAAAAUAGGAUAUAGUUUUGAUUUUUUUAAUUGUAAAAUAUUUUGGAGGGAGAACAAAAUCUUUUAACAUUUUGAAUAAAUUUAGAGUUUUAUAAAAUA